GGCGGAGCGGGUGCGUGCGGCGGCGGUUGCGAGAGAGAUGAGCCGCGGCGAUGAGCCCGGAAAAGCAGCACCGGGAAGAGGAUGAAGUUGACUCCGUUCUCCUUUCAGCGUCCAAGAUCCUAAAUUCUUCGGAGGGGGUGAAGGAAAGUGGCUGCAGUGACACAGAAUAUGGCUGCAUAGCAGAAUCAGAAAAUCAAAUCCAACCACAAUCAGCAUUGAAAGUCCUUCAGCAGCAGUUGGAAUCAUUUCAGGCUUUGCGAAUGCAGACUUUGCAGAAUGUCAGCAUGGUACAGUCGGAAAUCAGUGAAAUAUUGAACAAAAGUAUUAUUGAAGUAGAAAACCCACAAUUUAGCUCAGAAAAAAAUCUGGUGUUUGGCACGCGCAUUGAAAAGGAUUUGCCUACAGAGAAUCAAGAAGAAAACCUUUCUAUGGAGAAAAGUCAUCAUUUUGAGGAUUCCAAGACACUUCAUUCAGUGGAAGAAAAAUUAAGUGGUGAUAGUGUGAACAGUCUCCCUCAAAGUGUAAAUGUUCCAUCCCAGAUACAUUCCGAGGACACAUUAACUCUGAGAACUUCAACAGACAAUUUAUCUUCAAACAUAAUUAUACACCCUUCAGAAAAUUCUGACAUCUUGAAGAAUUAUAAUAACUUUUAUCGUUUUCUACCUACUGCACCUCCAAAUGUGAUGUCUCAAGCUGAUACAGUAAUUCUGGAUAAAUCCAAAAUUACUGUGCCUUUUCUCAAGCAUGGAUUUUGUGAAAAUUUAGAUGACAUUUGCCAUUCUAUCAAACAAAUGAAAGAAGAGCUUCAAAAGUCACAUGAUGGGGAAGUGGCACUUACAAAUGAACUUCAGACUUUACAAACUGAUCCAGAUGUUCACAGGAAUGGUAAAUAUGACAUGUCCCCUAUUCACCAGGAUAAAAUGAACUUUAUUAAGGAAGAAAACUUGGACGGUAACUUAAAUGAAGAUAUAAAAUCAAAGAGAAUUUCAGAAUUAGAGGCAUUAGUGAAGAAAUUACUCCCCUUCAGGGAAACUGUGUCAAAAUUCCAUGUGCAUUUUUGUAGAAAAUGUAAAAAGUUAUCUAAGAGUGAAAUGCACAGGGGAAAGAAAAAUGAGAAAAACAAUAAAGAAAUUCCCAUCACUGGCAAAAAUAUUACAGAUUUAAAAUUCCAUUCCAGAGUUCCAAGAUACACACUGUCCUUCCUCGACCAAACAAAACAUGAAAUGAAAGACAAAGAAAGACAACCAUUUCUAGUAAAACAAGGAUCAAUAAUAUCUGAAAAUGAGAAAACUUCCAAAGUUAAUUCCGUUACUGAGCAGUGUGUUGCAAAAAUUCAGUACUUACAGAAUUACCUAAAAGAAUCUGUGCAGAUACAGAAAAAAGUAAUGGAACUGGAGAGUGAAAAUCUAAACCUUAAGUCCAAAAUGAAACCUCUUAUCUUUACCACACAAUCUCUCAUACAGAAAGUUGAAACAUAUGAAAAGCAACUUAAGAAUCUGGUUGAAGAAAAGAGUACUAUUCAGUCUAAGUUAAGUAAAACAGAAGAAUACAGCAAAGAGUGUCUUAAAGAAUUUAAAAAAAUAAUUAGUAAAUAUAAUGUUCUGCAAGGCCAAAAUAAAACUCUAGAGGAAAAAAAUAUACAACUUUCUUUAGAGAAGCAACAAAUGAUGGAAGCAUUAGAUCAACUAAAAAGUAAGGAACACAAAACUCAAAGUGAUAUGGCCAUUGUAAAUAAUGAAAAUAAUCGAAUGAGUAUAGAAAUGGAAGCAAUGAAAACCAAUAUUCUGUUGAUACAAGAUGAAAAAGAAAUGUUAGAGAAAAAAACACACCAGCUUCUAAAAGAAAAAAGCUCACUUGGAAAUGAACUAAAAGAAAGCCAGCUAGAGAUAAUCCAGCUAAAAGAGAAAGAAAGAUUGGCAAAAACGGAACAAGAGACACUUCUUCAAAUAAUAGAAACAGUUAAAGAUGAAAAACUCAACCUUGAAACAACAUUACAAGAAUCUACUGCUGCCAGACAAAUUAUGGAAAGAGAAAUUGAGAAUAUUCAAACCUACCAAUCUACUGCCGAAGAGAAUUUUCUGCAAGAAAUAAAAAAUGCAAAAUCAGAAGCAAGUAUUUAUAAGAAUAGCUUGUCAGAAAUUGGCAAGGAAUGUGAAAUGUUAUCAAAAAUGGUAAUGGAAACCAAAACAGAUAAUCAGAUUCUAAAAGAAGAACUAAAGAAACAUAGUCAAGAAAAUAUAAAAUUUGAAAACAGCAUCAGUAGACUUACUGAAGACAAAAUACUUUUAGAAAAUUACGUAAGAAGCAUAGAAAAUGAAAGGGAUACCUUGGAAUUUGAGAUGCGGCAUCUUCAACGAGAAUAUUUAAGUUUAAGUGAUAAAAUUUGUAAUCAGCAUAAUGACCCUUCAAAAACAACUUACAUUUCAAGAAGAGAGAAAUUCCAUUUUGACAACUAUACUCACGAAGAUACUUCUAGUCCUCAGAGUAGGCCUUUGGCUUCGGAUUUGAAAGGUGGAAACAAUACACAUGCCUGCCCUGGCUCCAGAGGAAACACAAUCUCUAGCUUCCAAGGUUGCAAGCACACCUGUUCUGUGCUCCAGAGACACUCUGUCUUCCAAGACUGCUAUUCAAAUAUUCCUUGUUGAAUUCUGUCCAAAGCUUUUUCUACAUUUAUUGGAGGUGAUCCUGGUUUUUCUCCUUUAAUCUGUUAAUAUGGUAAAUUAUGUUAAUUUUGAAACACUAACCUUGAAUUCCUGGGAUAAACUCCACUGGGUGAUGUUGUAUUAUUCUUUUAAUAUACAUUCCUGGAUUCAAUUUGGUAAUAUUUUGUUAAGGAUUUCUGCUUCUGUAUUCAGAAGGAUGUUGGUCUGUAUUAUUUUCUUGUAAUGUCUUUGUCUGGCUUUGGCAUCAGGAAAAUCCUGUUGGGAAGUGUUUCCCCUCCUCUAUUUUCUGAAUUUGUGUAGGAUUGGUAUUAUUAAUAUUAUUCCUUCCUUAAAUAUUUAAAUAUGUAAUACUCAUACAUAUUUGUAAAAUAUAUAAUAUGUAAAUAUUCACCAGAGGGCCUGGAUUUUUCUAAAUGGGAAGGUUUUACAUUGCUAAAUGAUUUCUAUUAAUAUAGAACUACUCAGAUUUUCUAUUUCUUGAGUUAGAGUUGACAAUUUUGUAUGUUCUGAGGAAUUUGUACAUUUCAUGUAAGUUCUCAAAUGUAUUGUCACAAAGUUGUUCAUAAUAUUCCUUAUUAGCAUUUUAACGUUCAAAGGACUUGUAGCGAUGUCCCCUCUUUAAUUUCUGACAUUGGUAAUUUGGGGAUUCUUUUUUCUUUAUUAUUCUUGCUAGAGUUUUACCAAUUUUAUUUUUCUUUUCAAAAAAUCAGCUUAUUAUUUCAUUGAUUUUUCUUGCUGCUUUGUUUUUUUCUUCCAUUGAUUUCUGUUCCUAUUUAGUAAUUUCAUUCCUUUGGGUCGUCUGGUGCUACUUGGCUCCUUCCCUAGUUUCGUACCUGCAUUAAUAGCAUCACAGAGUCUG